AGUGCGUUACUUACCUCGACUCUUAGCUUGUCGGGGACGGUAACCGGGACCCGGUGUCUGCUCCUGUCGCCUUCGCCUCCUAAUCCCUAGCCACUAUGCGUGAGUGCAUCUCCAUCCACGUUGGCCAGGCUGGUGUCCAGAUUGGCAAUGCCUGCUGGGAGCUCUACUGCCUGGAACACGGCAUCCAGCCCGAUGGCCAGAUGCCAAGUGACAAGACCAUUGGGGGAGGAGAUGACUCCUUCAACACCUUCUUCAGUGAGACGGGCGCUGGCAAGCACGUGCCCCGGGCUGUGUUUGUAGACUUGGAACCCACAGUCAUUGAUGAAGUUCGCACUGGCACCUACCGCCAGCUCUUCCACCCUGAGCAGCUCAUCACAGGCAAGGAAGAUGCUGCCAAUAACUAUGCCCGAGGGCACUACACCAUUGGCAAGGAGAUCAUUGACCUUGUGUUGGACCGAAUUCGCAAGCUGGCUGACCAGUGCACCGGUCUUCAGGGCUUCUUGGUUUUCCACAGCUUUGGUGGGGGAACUGGUUCUGGGUUCACCUCCCUGCUCAUGGAACGUCUCUCAGUUGAUUAUGGCAAGAAGUCCAAGCUGGAGUUCUCCAUUUACCCAGCACCCCAGGUUUCCACAGCUGUAGUUGAGCCCUACAACUCCAUCCUCACCACCCACACCACCCUGGAGCACUCUGAUUGUGCCUUCAUGGUAGACAAUGAGGCCAUCUAUGACAUCUGUCGUAGAAACCUCGAUAUCGAGCGCCCAACCUACACUAACCUUAACCGCCUUAUUAGCCAGAUUGUGUCCUCCAUCACUGCUUCCCUGAGAUUUGAUGGAGCCCUGAAUGUUGACCUGACAGAAUUCCAGACCAACCUGGUGCCCUACCCCCGCAUCCACUUCCCUCUGGCCACAUAUGCCCCUGUCAUCUCUGCUGAGAAAGCCUACCAUGAACAGCUUUCUGUAGCAGAGAUCACCAAUGCUUGCUUUGAGCCAGCCAACCAGAUGGUGAAAUGUGACCCUCGCCAUGGUAAAUACAUGGCUUGCUGCCUGUUGUACCGUGGUGACGUGGUUCCCAAAGAUGUCAAUGCUGCCAUUGCCACCAUCAAAACCAAGCGCAGCAUCCAGUUUGUGGAUUGGUGCCCCACUGGCUUCAAGGUUGGCAUCAACUACCAGCCUCCCACUGUGGUGCCUGGUGGAGACCUGGCCAAGGUACAGAGAGCUGUGUGCAUGCUGAGCAACACCACAGCCAUUGCUGAGGCCUGGGCUCGCCUGGACCACAAGUUUGACCUGAUGUAUGCCAAGCGUGCCUUUGUUCACUGGUACGUGGGUGAGGGGAUGGAGGAAGGCGAGUUUUCAGAGGCCCGUGAAGAUAUGGCUGCCCUUGAGAAGGAUUAUGAGGAGGUUGGUGUGGAUUCUGUUGAAGGAGAGGGUGAGGAAGAAGGAGAGGAAUACUAAUUAUCCAUUCCUUUUGGCCCUGCAGCAUGUCAUGCUCCCAGAAUUUCAGCUUCAGCUUAACUGACAGACGUUAAAGCUUUCUGGUUAGAUUGUUUUCACUUGGUGAUCAUGUCUUUUCCAUGUGUACCUGUAAUAUUUUUCCAUCAUAUCUCAAAGUAAAGUCAUUAACAUCAAAA